UCAAGUAAUCCUCCUGCCUUGGCCUCCCAAGGUGCUGGGAUUACAGGUGUGAGCCACCACACCCAGCACAGAGUUGAGCAUUUCUCAGAAGCAUCUGUGCUGCUUAACACUGCAGAAUAUUAUGCAGAUGCACAGGGAAUAAAAAAUAUCUGCAGGUACACACACGCACACAGGUAUGUAACACACACACACGCACACACACACGUGCCUGCAGCUCCACGUGCCUGGCUCCCUGGUGGGGCUGCCGUCCUCCUCAUUCCUGGGGCCUCACACACGUGGGUGUUCGUUCCCUGGGGAAGCAAAAGUGGCUCAGGAGGCAGUGCAUCUGGCAGCCCCAGUAAGGCAGUGGGUCAGGGCAGGCUGGGCCGAGCUCUGGGGUGGGGCCUGCCCACAGCUGGUGCUCAGUCAGUGGGCGCUGCGGCCGGGGGAGCAGGAAUCACAGAAUUACCUGAAAGCUUCUUCCGGUCUCUGCCCUGAAGACCUAGGAAGCUGAUUUCACAGAUGUCCCAGGUGAUUGCCCAUUAGGCCAGGUUUGGGACCCCCUGGUUUUGGGAUAAGGGUGGGGAGAGGAGGUAGAAGCCCUCGAGCAGCUCCAGGGAGCAUCCUCCUGGGAGUGGAAUUGAGGGAGGGAGGAGCCCAUGCCAGAAACCUGGAGGACAGCCCCGAGACAGUGGGGGCAGCAGCCCUGGGGGGUGCAUCUGUGGGAGAUCGCGUGUUGGGUGUCCCACAGUGGACUUUGUGGUGGUCUCCUUUACUGAUGAAGCGUGGAGCUCUGACAAGUGACCGCCAUGCUUGUGUGGGGUGCCGCCUGUGGUUCCAUGUUGCUGUGAACACAGCUAGUCCACUACCAGACGGAAGGGGACUUCUGAAGGUGAUUACUGGGGCUUCAGUAAAUGCAAUGCAAAUCGGCCAAUACCUGUUUUUAAGGACCUAUAUCCCAAAACAAACACAACUGCAGCAAGGCUUAGAAACAGCCAGACUCAGGAGCCCAGGCGGCCCCUAACCCGAAUCUCUUACUGUAAUUGACAUCCAUCUUGGGAAAAUCCUACUGGGGCAGUAACUCAGGGCAAUGUUGUUGUUUUCCACGUCAUUUCUGAGUGUUUCAGCUCUGUUUUGUCCUUAGAGAGUUAGUGUACUCUGCUGCCAGAAGGCAGCCACUAGAAACUUUCAUCUUGCAGCUGCACAUAAAAAGAUCAAAAACUGAAGUUCAUAGGUCAUAACCAUUUGAGAUGUUUGUCAGGUUUGCCUUAUUGAGUAAAAUAAUAGAACUGUUGUGAGUUUGUCUUUCCAACAUCAUGUUGACUUGUUGGAGGAGUUUGCAUCAGCACUCUUGUUCCGACGGUUGGAGGACUCGAGGGUGCUUUGCCCUGUUUCUUUUUGGCUUUGAUAGUGAAAGGAUCCUCCCGUGGGACCCACAUUCCCAGGCUUCUCUGGUGUCUUGCUCUAAGUGAGCUUAUGCAGGGCGGGAAGGUGGCGGGCACUGGAUAUAAAUGGGGAGUUCUUUAGCCCCUGCUUUGGGGUGGGUGUCUGAGUCCCAGUUAUGAUUGACGGGAUGAUCAGUGUCCUGUGUGUGUGGCGCCUGGUGUGCUCAGAGACCUGGACACCAUUCUGGUCUGAGCACAGCCCCAUGCUCGUGUGCAGGCUGAGCAGUGGGAAUGAGAAGCCCAGGGAGGCCCUGAGGGAUGGCGGCCUCCCUGCCCCUCAGGCUGGCAAGCCGGGGCAUCAUUUGUUUUAUGUUUUUUUGCAGGGACAAAGGAAUUAAUAGAGUAACACGGGUAAAAAAUGCAGAGAAAGCAAAGGAAGAUGCCAAGAGUGAUGAGAGGGGUGACUUGGAACAAAUCUGUGUGUGGAGGUGUCUGAGCUCUUGGGAGUGGCUGGGGGCUCAUGUGACGUUGCAGGAUGCCCGCCUCAGCAUAACAGCACCCUGAGCGCAGGCUCAGGUCAGGCCCACCUCACUGGAAUCCUGGCCACGUGAUGGGUGUCUCACCUCACCUCUCUGAACCUCAGUCUCCUCUUCGUACAGAGUGAAAACCUCGUCCUCAUGGUGGUGGUGCUUUGAUCAGAGGAGAUGAUGCGGGCGACCUGCAGUUGUGUCCCACAUGCAGGGCCCUCAGAAGGUCCCUCUGAUGGUGACUGUUACUCCCGCCGUGAUGGGGGCGUUACUCUGCCUGGCAGUAGGGCGGGCGUUCCUCCUCCCUUUGAUCCCCUUUGUUGACCUCUGGGUCUUUACUUUGCAAGCAGGGAGGGAUAAGAAAACAUUUAAAAAGGCUUAUCUCUGAUAAAUAACACUCAUCUGUCUGGUGUCCACAGCGGCCUUGAGAGGCUCGGGCCAGGGACACAGAAGAUGGCCUGUGUCGCUCAGAACUCACCUCUAUACAGACCCAGGUGCGCCGGACCCCGACAGCUCUUGGGGACCUUCCUUGCCCGCUCGUAGACAGGAGCGACGCCGAAAGGGCGCCAGCUGUGCCCCCCCGGGCCAUGAACCCAGCUGAAGCCGGUGGAACUAGAAGGCCACGUGCUGCCCAUGGCUUUGCCGUGGUGGCUCGAGUGGCCCUAUUGGUGACUGGGGCAGGGGGGCCUUGCUGGGCGCACCUUGGUCCCUGUGCGUGCUGCUGCUUCGUGAAGUAUGCAGUUUGCCAGAUGCUAAAGCGCGUGCCUCACUGUAAGAACGGUCACAUUAGGUGUGGAUGGAUUCUCAGUGCUGAGACGCUCACUCAUCACACCUUAACUUCGCUGUUGGCCCUGGAAGCUUUUUGGGGGGUGGUCCCUGUUCUGUGCAGCUCCCCUGAGGAGUGCAGAGCAUUCUCCUGGAAUGUUCUGAAACAUUUGAGGGUGACCCUGUGGACAUAGCCUGGCCAUUCCAGGACUGGCAGGUGAACACAGGAUCUGGUCGGGGAUGCGCAUGGUAGAGUCGGCGGGAACUCUGGUUGGACUCCCUCUGGGAAGCUUUGCAAAGGAUAUGCCAUUGGAAGGAGCCAGGCCGGGGGUGAGGCCCGUUCAUGGUGUGUGAUUGAGGAGAGGGCUUGGGGGCAGCAUCAAAACAGGACUCACCAGUGAGCCAGGUGUAAAGCACCCCCUGGAUACGAGGGAUGAAAGACCAUGGUUGAGCAGGGUCAGGGGCUGGGGCUGGGGAGGGGCGAGUUGCCUGGUGGUCAGCACAGGCCCACCAAGAAAGAGUAGGACUGGACAGGGGUCAGUGGCUCACGCCUGAAAUCCCAGCACUUCGGGAGGCCAAGGCGGGCGGAUCACCUGAGGUCAGGAGUUUGAGGCCAGCCUGGCUAACGUGGUGAAAACCCGUCUCUACUAAAAAUACAAAAAUUAGCCGGGCAUGGUGGCAGGCGCCUGUAAUUCCAGCUACCCAGGAGGUGGAGGUUGGAGCGAGCUGAGAUCGCGCCACUGCACUCCAGCAAAGGAGGGAUGCAGCCAGGGCCCAGGUGCAGGCUGAGGGCAGGGAGAUCAAUACCAGGGACGUGCAGCAGGGACUGAGCAGAGGAGGGACGCCAGCUGACUUAGUCUUUAAAAGGAUCCCUGUGGCCACUGUGUUAGAAACAGACCAAGAGGGUGGGGUGGAAGCAGGGAGGCCUUCCUGGAGGAGGCUGCUGGGAUGGUCCCAGUGGAGGGCAUGCUCUGGAGCAAGGGGGCCGUUGGAAGGAGCGGGAUGGGGGUGUGUGCCAUGCACUAUCCCCCGCCUCCAGCAUGGUCUGUCUGUGGUUGAUGCUGCUUCUCUUUGAGCCUCGUCCCGUUUCCCGUUUCUCAUUGCAGAUCCCAGUGGCAUCGUCUUGUUGACAGAUGUUUCAGAAGAUGUCACCACAUGACAUGGGUGUGUGUCUGUCUUCCUCUGUGCUCCUUAUAUGCCCCGCAUAGUGUCCGGCAUCCGAAGUCCAACCCUUCCUCCCAGCCGGGGAGCACACGGUGCCAGAGUUGCCCGUUGCUCACUGGUGUGGAUGUUCGCAGUUGGUGGCCUCGGAAUGCGAGGACCAGAGCCUCCUCCUGAGCCCCCAGCCUUGCUGUUAGUUGGGGACGCUGGCUGCUCAGUGCUGCCGUCUCCCGCAGCUGCAUCUCCUGGGUGUAGCCCGGCGUGCCCUCUGUUCCGAGUGUCUUUCUUGCAGAUUGGUGGCCGGAGCUGGAGGGGUGUUUGGAUGCAGGCUCUCCAAGUUUGGGUUUGUUCUGCCACUGUCCAUCCCUGUCCAGGGUGAGGUGGUCACUGCCACGCACGCCGGCUCUGUGCCCUGAGGUGCGUGCAGUGUGGACGUUCUGGCUCCACUUCUACAAAUGGGGACUCGCCCUGCUUGGCUGUUUGGGGUGUGCUUGAAGGCAGGGGGCAAGGCUGGCCCAGGUGGGCUGCCUCCCAGAGUGAGGCAGGGCUCCAGAGGGGGCAGAGCCGGGUGACCCAGUCGAGACCUGCUGGGUGGGGGCUCUUCGGAGCUGGCCUGAGGACAGUGGGUGCCACCCAUGCAAGCCAGUGUGAGUGUCUGUUAUGGACAAGCUUGGUUCCAGAAACCCAGGAGGGGACGGUCCAUCGCGCUCGCCCUGCACCUUCCUGGCUCCCCGUGCAUCUCGCCCUAUGGUGGGCUCUCCUGUCCUGUCUCCAUCACCCACUGUGACCUCCUUGCCCCGGGAUCAUCUUGGUUCCCUUGUGUCUAUGCAGUGUUCGCCAUGUGUCUUCUUUAACUCACUAAAGGCUUACUGCCUUUAGUCAUUUCUUUGUUUAAGAGUUAAAUCUGCAUGUUGAAACUCGCUUACCCUUUUGAAAAGUUCUGCAGCCAUCCCGCCCUGGGGCCUCUUUUUCUUGUGGUUUGUGGCUCGGUGGCAAGUGGCCUCCCAGGGCUGUGUUUGGGAUGGGAGAUGACGUCUGUGGCCUGGCAGGGGUGAUGAUGGUGGCCAUUAUGGAGGGAGGGGCCAUGGGGCUGCAUCCAUAGCACUGAUGGAGACAGGUAACAGGUGUGCACGGGAGGGAAGCAUGGCCACAUCAGGGGGCACGCAGCAAGACGGCACCCUCCGCUCCCACCAGCCCUGCCCUUCUGGAUGUUGCUAGGUCCAGGUGUGACCCGUGUCCAGCCGGGGGCCUGACUGCUGACUGGCUGCUGGAGGCUGACUGCCUCCCUGUGUGCCCUCAGGAGACAGGCCAAGGCUGGAGUGCCGGGGGACGUGUGGCAGUGACAUCGGAUGAACCAUUGUAAGAUGAACAAUUCAGUGGCGUGUAGCGCAUUCACAGUGUGGUGCAGCCAUCAUCGCUGUCUACUUCCAAACCGCUUCAUUCCCCCAAGAGGAGACCCCAUGUGCAUUAUUCCCCCAAGAGGAGACCCCAUGUGCAUUAUUCCCCCAAGAGGAGACCCCAUGUGGAUUAUUACCCCAAGAGGAGACCCCAUGUGCAUUAUUCCCCCAAGAGGAGACCCCAUGUGGAUUAUUCCCCCAAGAGGAGACCCCAUGUGCAUUAUUCCCCCAAGAGGAGACCCCAUGUGCAUUAUUCCCCCAAGAGGAGACCCCAUGUGCAUUAUUCCCCCAAGAGGAGACCCCAUGUGCAUUAUUCCCCCAAGAGGAGACCCCAUGUGCAUUAUUCCCCCAAGAGGAGACCCCAUGUGCAUUAUUCCCCCAAGAGGAGACCCCAUGUGCAUUAUUCCCCCAAGAGGAGACCCCAUGUGCAUUAUUCCCCCAAGAGGAGACCCCAUGUGCAUUAUUCCCCCAAGAGGAGACCCCAUGUGCAUUAUUCCCCCAAGAGGAGACCCCAUGUGCAUUAUUCCCCCAAGAGGAGACCCCAUGUGCAUUAUUCCCCCAAGAGGAGACCCCAUGUGCAUUAUUCCCCCAAGAGGAGACCCCAUGUGCAUUAUUCCCCCAAGAGGAGACCCCAUGUGCAUUAUUCCCCCAAGAGGAGACCCCAUGUGCAUUAUUCCCCCAAGAGGAGACCCCAUGUGGAUUAUUCCCCCAAGAGGAGACCCCAUGUGGAUUAUUCCCCCGAGAGGAGACCCCAUGUGCAUUAUUCCCCCGAGAGGAGACCCCAUGUGCAUUAUUCCCCCGAGAGGAGACCCCAUGUGCAUUAUUCCCCCGAGAGGAGACCCCAUGUGCAUUAUUCCCCCGAGAGGAGACCCCAUGUGCAUUAUUCCCCCGAGAGGAGACCCCAUGUGCAUUAUUCCCCCGAGAGGAGACCCCAUGUGCAUUAUUCCCCCGAGAGGAGACCCCAUGUGCAUUAUUCCCCCGAGAGGAGACCCCAUGUGCAUUAUUCCCCCGAGAGGAGACCCCAUGUGCAUUAUUCCCCCAAGAGGAGACCCCAUGUGCAUUAUUCCCCCAAGAGGAGACCCCAUGUGGAUUAAGUAGUCACCCCCAUUCGCUCCCACCCAGCCCCUGGGAACUACCCAUCUGCGUUCCGUCUCACUGGAUUGACCUGUUCCGAGUAUGUUCUAUAGAUGAAGCCACACAGCCAGUGAACUCUUGUGUCUCCUUCUUUCACUCGGCAUGUCUUCACGGUUCACACGGCAGCAUCAGUGUUUCAUUUCUUUUUGUCAUCAAGUAUCCGAGUGUAUGGAUAUGUCCCAGUUCAUCUACGAUUUGGCUUGUUUCCACCUUUUGACUAUUGUAAAUAGUGCUGCUGUGAGCAUUUGUGUACAAGUUUUCCUGUGGACGUGUGUGUUCAUUUCUCAUGGGCUAGGUGAGAUGGUCACUCUGUGUUUAACUUUUUGAGGGCCCACUUAGCUGUUGUACAGUGGCUGCACCGUUUCCAUUCCCGCCAGCAGUUCACGAAGGGUUCAGUUUCUCCGCGUCCUCAUCAACACUUGUUACUAUCCUCUGAACCUUUUAGAAAGUGAACCAUACUAAACCAUUUCUAGCAGAUUAGUUGCCAGGAUGGAAAAAAAUGUUAGAUUUAAGAUGUUUUGCCCAGAUCACCUAAUAGAUAUUAGAUGUGUUCAUUUCUUCAUGCCAGAGUGUACAGCAUACUUGGAACCUGGAUGACUAAAUGAACGUAAUAAAGGUGAACAUCAUUGAACAAGGCCGAAAAGGGAGUCCGGUACCCAGACUCCAUCCUGGAUGCCUCAUAUGUCAAAGAAGCUUGUUCUUUGAGUCAGUGUUGAGUGACAGCUAUGUGCUGGGGUCAUGCCCGUGACUGGGGACAAUGGUGAAUGGACACAGUCUUGGCUUCUGCCUUGCGAGCUCACGGUCUGAGUCAUGAACACAGAUGUGAGUCUGUGAGCAGUCACUCACAAAUCCAUGGAAAAUGGCAGGUGUCUCCAGUGCAAGCAAGUGCUUGGUCCAGUAGGAGGGGCAGGAAAGUGGCCUGGAGCAUGGGGUGUCGGGGACUGCUGCGGCCAGAGGCUGCCAGGGAACGGCCAUCAUCAUCCAGCCCAAGGAGGGGCAAGUGUGGGAGACAGGCAGGCCCACCGGCUGCAGGGUGGAAAACGAUUGGCAGGUGGCUUGGAGAUCAUCAGAAAUGGCACCUGUGAGGGCAACUGUGGGUGGAGAGAUGGAGCAAAUGUGGCGUGAGGGAGAGGCUGCUGCCCAUAGAACUUCUGCUCCUUUGGCAUGGAUGGGCACAAUUCAGGAGGCAGGGAGAUCGCUUGAACCCAGGGGUCCAGGCUGCAGUGAGCUGUGAUCAUGCCAUUGCACUCCAGCCUGGGUGAUGGAGCGGGACCCUGUCUCUUUUUUAAAAAGAAAAGGAGACCAGAUUUACGUUGAAUUUGCAAACUUUGAGAAAAAUUUUUUUUUUCUUUUUCUUGGGGACAGGGUCUUACUCUGACAACCAAGCUGGCUUGCAGUGGCACAAUCUCAGCUCAGUGCAGCCUCUGCCUCCCUUGCUCAAACGAUCCUCCUGCCUCAGCCUCCCACAGAUGCAUGCCACCAUGCCUGGCUAAUUUUUUUGUAUUUUUUGUAGAGACAGGGUCUCUCCAUGUUAGCCUGGGCUGGUCUCAAACUCCUGAGCUCAAAGUGAUUUGCCUGCCUCAGCCUCCUAAAGUGCUGGGAUUACAGGCAUGAGCCACCGUGCCCGGCCGAGAAGAAGUUUUAAAGGGCUUUUUAUUGUGGAAAAAUUCAAAUGUACAUAAAAGUGGAGGAGAAGAUAUAAGGAACACUCAUGUGGCCAUCACUCAUCCUGUCCUCCUCUCCUGCUCCGCACCCUCCAUAGUUUGAGUCAUAUCAUUUCAUUCAUAAAUAUUCUCUUACCAUUUUACUUGACAAUGAUUUUAGGCUUACAGAAAAGUGGCCAGAGUAGUGCAGGGCUCCUAUAGUUGGCUUCCCCUGUUGCCAUCAUCUCGUCUGAUCGUAGGGCAGGUUAGCAUUGCUACAGGCCUCUUACCCGGCCUACAGCUCUUAGGCACAUCUGUCCAUUUGACUAAUGGCCAUUUUCUGGAUAGUCCAUGCUCACUUCUGGAGCCCCCUCCCACCCAGGCUCCCACAUGGCCGGUGCUGUUGCCUGAAGGCCCCUCUUCCUCCUGACGUGGGACCCCUUCAGGUAGCCCCGCAUCUUUUCAGCGUGCCCCUUCACAUUCUGACUGUUCCUCUCCUGGAACCUGCAAGAUGCUCUGGGAUCCUUGUAUUUUUCCUGCACCAGCCCGUUUCAUCCCUGAGCUUCUGUUAUUUUAUUGGAGGAUGGUGCUAGAAACACAGGUCUGGAUGCAGGCAGGAGACACACGCGUCCACACUAGCAUGCGUGUGUACACACAUCUACAUGUGCUUAUCCCCCGCGUUCAUGUUAAAAACCAUGGGAUCAUACCGGUGUUUCAGAUUCACAUCCACCCCAGCAGGGUUUCUCGCCUCCCCCAUUGCUUAUAACCUUAGCAGGUGUUGAGAACCCUGGCGCUCACUGUCCACAGUGAGUUUGCUUAUUCGUUGAAACCUAGCGUGCCUGUAGAGUGUGGAGAGUUGCCGGCCCGCACCCCUGCGAGACACAGACUUUCUGACCGCAGCCCUCAUGUGUGUGGCUCUUCUUGUCCUUGGCCUUACAGUGCAGUCGGAUCGCUGCUUUCCAGAGUUGCCUGGGGGUAGGUCCCUCCUCUUCUGUGCUCUGCGGCGCAGUGAGCGGCCUUUGCCUCAGGCCUCCCGCGGCUUCCUUAAGCCUCUGGCCUGCCCGGUCCCUGGCGCCAGGUCUGUUUUCCCUGCUCCCUUCUCUCUGAUCCUGCUUUGGUCUGAGCCGUGCCUCUGGGCCCCAGCAUUGCUGGGCCGCAUUGUCGUUUUAUUUCUCUUGUGUCGUUGCGUCUAGUGUAAGACAUUCAGUGGAUCAUUGUGGAUGGUCAUUAGUGGUCCAGAGUGGAAAGUGAGGUCGUUGUUGGUGGUGUACUUACAGUGCCUGUUAGGGAGCUGUUCCUGGUGUUGCCCGUGAAUAUUAGACUUGCUCCCGAGCCUGCGCCACAGCCCAUCCCUAGCGACUUGGCGACAGUGGCUGCCAGGUGCGGGUGGCUGUGUCUUGUAUACACUGUGUGGGCAGCCCAGGGCCAGGGGCCUCCUCCUUCCAUGGCAGCCUCUGUCUGCAUCACAGAGAUAAGGCCGCGGCUGCCACCAGGAUAAGGAGCCAGCAGCUGCUCUCGGAGGAGCCGCCCUGACCCCUCCCCAUCAUGCCGCCGUGGGGUUUCCAUGCAGAAUUUUCCUUGGGCAGAGUUGCUUUUUGAUUCUAGUUUUUAAAAAAACUGUUCUUUCCAUCAUGAUAAAAAGAAAGACAUGCUCAUUUCAAAUAGUUUAGGAGAUGUGGAAGUAAAAAGAAAAAAAAAACCACCUGUAAUAUUACUCACAAGAAAUAUGUUUUCUUUUCUUUUCUUUUUUUUUUGAGACAAGGUCUCACUCACCCAGGCUGGAGUGCAGUAAUACAAUCACGGCUCACUGCAGCCUUGGCCUCAGGAGACCCUCCCACCUCAGCCUCCCAGGUAGCUGGGACUGCAGGUGCACCCCGCCACCCUGGCUGAUUUUUUGUGUUUUUUGUAGAGACGGGUUUUCACCAUGUUGCCCAGGCUCACACAUUUCUAUACAUGGGUGGACAGUUGGGAUCAGCCACAUUUAUGAUUUUCUGUCUUUCCUUUUCACUUAAUGUCUUCAGCAGUUCUGAGUGCUGUUAAUUUGGGGGAAGCAUAUUUGUAUAUUUACAAUAGUUCUGGGUUUUUUAAGGUCUUGCUUUGUCACCCAGGCUGGAGUGCAGUGGCACAGUCACAGCUAACUGUAGCCUCAACUUCCUGAAUUCAAGUGUUUCUCCUGCCUUGGCCUCCCAAAGUGCUGAGAUUAUACGUGUGAGCCAUUACCCUUGGCCAACUUUUUUUUUUUUUUUUCCUGAGACGGAGUCUUGCUCUGUUGCCUAGGCUAGAGUGCAGUGGCACGAUCUCGGCUCACUGCAACCUCUGCCACCUGGGUUCAAGCGAUUCUCCUGCCUUAGCCUCCCAAGUAGCUGGGAUUACAGGCGCCCACCACUGUGCCAGGCUAAUUUUUUAUUUUUAGUAGAGACGGGGUUUCACCGUGUUGGCAGGGUUUCACCGUGUUGGCCAGGCUGGUCUCGAACUCCUGACCUCGUGAUCUGCCCGUCUAGGCCUCCCAAAGUGCUGGGAUUACAGGCGUGAGCCACCAUGCCUGGCCCAACUUUUUUUUUUUGUAGACGGUCUCACUCUGUUGCCCAGGCUGGAGUGCAGUGGUGCAAUCACGGCUCACAGCAGCCUCAACCUCCCAGGCUCGAGCAAUCCUGCCACCUCUUGAGUAGCUGGGACUACAGGUGUGUGCCACCACACCUGGCUUUUUUAUUUUUUAGUAGAGACAGGGUCUCACUAUGUUGUCCAGGCUGCUCUCAAACGCCUGGGCUCAAGCAGUCCUGCCACCUCAGCUUCCUAAAGUGCUGGGAUCACAGGCCUGAGCCACCAUGCCCAGCAUCCAACAAUUUUUAAAGUAAAAGGAUGAUGGCAGCACACAGAUCAGAGGGUGGGCUCCUGUGGGACAGGGUCACGCCCACGGGUGGCUGUGCUCAGUUCUUGAUUAUCCUCCACCUACCAGCUGCGUGACCGACAUUGGUGUCAUCAAAACUCUUCAUUUGGGCAUAAGAGUGGUGUUUCUCGGCCAGGCGCAGUGGCUUACGUCUGUAAUCCCAGCACUUUGGGAGGCUGAGGCAGGUGGAUCACUUGAGGUCAGGAGUUCAAGACCAGCCUGGCCAACAUGGUGAAACCCCGUCUCUACUAAAAAUACAAAAAAAUAGCUGGGCAUGGUGGCAGUUGCCUGUAGUCCCAGCUAUUCAGGAGGCUGAGGCAGGAGGGUCACUUAAACCCUGGAGGUGGAGGUUGAAGUGAGCUGAGAUCUGCACCCCAGCCUGGGCGACAGAGCGAGACUCCAUCUCGAAAAAAAAAAAGAGUGGUGCUUCUCUCACAGGGUCACUGAGAUUGAACAGGUCAAUGCGCCCGAGAGCCUGGUGUACAGCAGGUGCUCGCGUUAGCUGCUAGUUGUGUUGUUGUUGUUUCUCUUACAUAUAUGCUUAGAACACCCUCUUUUUCAGAGUGCUUCCUUACAGGGUCUGACAAGGUGUGUGGGGAUGAGGGGGGUCCACUCUCUCACUGCCAGAGGCUGGACCUGCUCCUGCUGCAUCUCCGAUCCAGCAUCGUUGCUUGCAGAGAGCAGAGCUGCAGGAAGCAUUUGGUGGAGGGUGCGCGGGGGUGGAGAGCGGGGCCAGGGAUGGACAGGCUGCCUGGUGAAAACACGCAGGGCUCCGCUGGACGCAGUCAGUGCUGAUGUGUGUCUCUUUCCUGAGGGCCACUUACAGAUGUUCCUUGUAAAUCCACCUGUGCUCAGCCCCUGCUGGGUGGAGGCUGUACCCCAAGGCCGAGUGAGGUGGGGGCAGUGAGCUCUCUCCCCCUGAGGCUCUCCUGUUCUGUGAGCCUGGUAUUGGGCAGUUCUAGGGGCUCUGGCACCGAGGCCCUGGACUCCCACCCAGGCCCUGCCCACUGCUGCUGCCCCUGUGUCAGCUCCUCCUCUGUAAAAUGGGAUAAUAAUAGUGAUUGCCAUCAUUAAUUCUUAUAAAUAAUACCCAUGUGCUAAUAUGAAAUUAUGUAUCAUAACCAUCAGAAUAUGACCAUAAUGCAUUGUAUUUUAUUAUAAUUUAGUUAUGAGCAAUUGUUGAUUAUAAUUCAUUGCAAUUAUUAUCAAUAAGUGAUUGUGUUAAUUACAUAAUAGUUACUAGAGUUAAUAAUUGUUGUCGUUGUCAUAAUUAGUAACGGGAUUACACUGUGGGAGUGAAGUGAAUUAAUGCAUGGCAAAUCUUCCUUGUGCAUAGGAAGCCGUUGGUGCCUGCGGCUCGCUGUUGCGAUAAUGGCUGUGUAAGUGGGUGGCGGGGCUGUCAUCGGUCCUUUGAGGAGUGAGCCUCUCCUGUAGGAAUCUCAAAAUGAUGCUUCAGUAAGUUUGUGCUGGUGCUGCCUGGAUAAAGCAGGGUACAGAUGGGAUGGCGGUUAGGGUUCCCUGAGGAGUCUCGUCUGGCACAGACUAUGGGGUGUGGGAGCCUCACGGGCUUGGUUACAAGGGUUCUUGUACAAGAAUGUGGAAGACUCAGUGCAAACCUUGUUCUGAGGAAGGCACAUGCUCUGAGGGUGAGCCUGUUGGCUUAGGGCUCGCUGAUGACAGGGUACGCAUUGAUUCAGAUGAAUGAUAUCAGAAAGCAUGUUUCUUACAAAAUGCCCUCAGAAUGGGAACAGAUAUCUUUUGUUCUUUUAAGUGACUUUGCAGGUAUUUGGUCCCAUUGUUUGCUUGGAUAUUGUCAAAGUUUGUUUUCUAAACAAAGCCCCAGAGAGACAGAGCAAACACAUGAGUGCUCCAACUCAAUAGUGUGUUUAAUUCAGAACAGACCGUGGGCAGGAUCUGUGGCGAAGCCGCGUGGAGAGCUGCCACAGGCAUGAGCAAGCAAGAGGGUGGUCCGGUUCCGAAAAGCAAAACCACCUUGAGCGUGGUAAAAGUUUCAUUUAACUGUGGCUGCCCCCUAAACAUCGGCUGUAGUGGACAGAAGCCACCAUUUCCUACCUGAUGUCAGCCACUUCUAUUCUGUCCCUGAAGUGUCAGCUCCUGGCCAGGCGGUGGGGCAGGCCCCACUUCAUGCUGGUUCUGUGGCUUUGAACUCACGAGCCUGCCACCCUUCAGAGGGCUCUGAGCGGGCUGUGUGCCGGGCGAGAACACUGCCUGGGCCGGGGCCACUGUGGCAUGAGAAGGGCCGCCUGGGGGCCCGGGGCCUAGAGCAGGUGGGCAAGGAGUGGGUGCUGACUAUGUCUGCUCUGGGCCUUCGGCGCUGAGUCUUACAGGCCUGGCCAGGGGGCUGUCUCCAUUAUUUCACUCCAUUUUUGUUUAUUUUAUUUUGGUUUGCUUUGUUUAUAAUAUUUUAUUUUGAGACAGGAUCUUACUCUGUUGCCUGGGCUGGAGUGGAGUGGCACGAUCUCGGCUCACUGCAGCCUUGACUUCCUGGGCACAAGGGAUCCUCCCAUCUCAGCCUCCCAAAGUGCCGGGAUUACAGACAUGAGUCACUGCACCAGCCUGCUUUUGUUUAUUUCAAAAGUGGAACGUUUUAAAUGCUGUGUUUGGCAAAUCAGGACUCAUAAAACAGUUAGUGGAAUUGUGCUGUGGAUAAUGAAUAUGUGAAUGGUGGUGUUGGCAGGGAGUGGUCCCAGGCUUGUAUGUGAUGAAAAGAUGUUACCAAGAGUCACACAGAUGAAGUCUGAGGCUCCAGGAGUGACUUGAGCGGUUAGAGUGAGUUCUCAUGACUUCAGUAACAGCAGCAGCAGCAGUUACCGAGGGCACGGCGAAUGCUGAGUGCCAGGUGCUUGCAAAGGGCUUUAGGCGGUCAUGACUCUGUGGGUCCUGCCAUCCUCCCGUUUUGGAAGUGAGGAGACUGGGGCACAGAGGGGUUCAGGUCACGCAGCAGUAAGUACUGGAUCCUGGAUUCAGACCUGGUGGUGCCUCCAGGUUCUAGAACCUUGACUCGUGUGGCUCCUGGUCUGGUUGUUGGACCCCAGGCCCGGAAGGACGCCUUAGUAGAGUGUGGGCUGCAUUGUCACUGCAACAGGUUGCUGAAGACAUGAGGAGAGUAGCUUGCAUUCCUUUGCCAUAAUUAUGCAAACGUGCAGGACUUUUAGGGGACCUCUCUGAAAUAGAGCAAACUUCAUUAGGGAAUCAAAGGAAAAGAUUGGCUCAGAAUUUAGUGGGUUUGGAUUUCCCAGUGUUUUCAUUAAAGAAUUGGUUUAAUGUGUUUUUCUUAGGACACUGUUUUGAAUAAAUGAAUAUUGACUUGAGUCCUGCCUUUGCUUUUGUUUUGUUUUGAGACGGAGUCUCACUCUGUCUCCUAGGCUGGAGUGCAGUGGCACGAUCUCGGCUCACUGCAACCUCUACCUCCCGGUUUCAAGCAGUUCUCCUGCCUCUGCCUCCCGAGUAGCUGGGACUACUACAAGCACACGCCACGCCCAGUUAAUUUUGUAUUUUUAGUAGAGACAGGGUUUCACCAUGUUAGCCAGGAUGGUCUUGAACUCCUGACCUGAGAGAUGAUCCGCCCGCCUUGGCCUCCCAAAGUGCUGGAAUUACAGGCGUGAGCCACCGUGUCUGGCCUUUUUUUUUUUUUUUUUUUUUUUUUGAGACAGGGUCUUGCUCUGUUGCCCAGGCUGGAGUGCGUUGGGGAUGAUCAUGGUUCACUGCAGUUUCAACCUCCUGCACUCAAGCGAUCUCACUUCAGCCUCCUGAGUAGCUGGGAUCACAGGCAUGCACCACUACAUCCGGCUACUUUAAAAAUUUUUGUUGUGGAGACGAGGUCUCUCUGUGUUGCCCAGGCUGGUCUCAAGCCCCAGGGGUCAAGUGACCCUCCUGCCUCGGCUUCCCUAAGUGCUGGGAUUAUAGGUGUGAGCUACCAUGCCUGGCCAGCUGUUCUUUAUAGUGUGAUAGAAACCAGACCCGAAUUUCUGCAGUGGUCUUGUGGAUAGAGUUCCAUUUGUCGCCGAUUCUGCCAGUAUUACCGUUAUUCCUGAAGAAACCUCAGGCAGGGCUGCUGUGUUUUUAAGAAAAUACUCUAGAUGACAAUCCACUCCUGGAAAGGGACAUUCAGACGGCAGCUCUUCAGCUGUUUUUGGUUGGGACCUCUUUACAUUCUUAAGUUAUUGAGAACCCCGAAGACCAUUUGUUUAUGUGGGUUAUAUCUGUUGUAUUACAAAUUAAAACAGGAGUUUAAAAAACAUUUGAUACAACAACAUGUCAUUAUAUUAAAUAUGUAUUCAUAUAAAUGUUUUUAUGAAAGAUAAUUUCUUCUAAAACAAAAUAUAAUGAGAAGAGUGGCGUAGUUUUACAUUUUUCCUAAAUCUCCUUAAGGUCUGCCUUAAUAGAAAGCAUCAGCUGGCUUCUGCAUUCUGUCGACAGGGAUAUGUUGGGGUUUUUUUGUUUUUUGUUGCUGUUGUUUUUUGAGACGGAGUCUUGCUCUGUCGCCCAGGCUGGAGUGCAGUGGCGCUAUCUCGGCUCACUGCAAGCUCCGCCUCCCGGGUUCACGCCAUUCUCCUGCCUCAGCCUCCCGAGUAGCUGGGACUACGGGCGUCUGCCACCACACCUGGCUAAUUAUUUUGUAUUUUUAGUGGAGACGGGGUUUCACCGUGUUAGCCAGGAUGGUGUCGAUCUCCUGACCUCGUGAUCUGCCCACCUCGGCCUCCCAAAGUGCUGGGAUUAAAGACGCGAGCCACCAUGCCUGGCCAGGGAUAUGUUGUUUUGGUUGAAGUAUAAAAAAAAAAAUCUGGCCUCAUGCAGCUAUGUAGCUGGAAGGGAGGGUUGUUGUUGUAGCCUUUUCAGAUAAUUAUGGGUAUUUGUUGCUACUACACCAAAACUCGAAAAACAGUAGUUUCAUUUUGUUUUUUUUGAGACCGAGUUUUUUGGGUCUUGUUGCCCAGGCUGGAGUGCAGUGGCGCAGUCUCGGCUCACUGCAACCUCCGCCUCCUGGGUUCAAGCGAUUCUCCUGCCUCAACCUCCGAGUAGCUGGGAUUACAGCCACCACACCCGGCUAAUUUUAUAUUUAUAGCAGAGAUGGGGUUUCACCAUGUUGGCCAAGCUGGUCUCAAACUCCUCGUGUGAUCCACCUACCUCAGCCUCCCAAAGUGCUGAGAUUACAGGCGUGAGCCACCACACCCAGCCAGAAAAAGCAAUAGUUUCUUGAAAGUCAGGUGCAGUGUAGAAUCCGCAGCUGUAGAACUGCAGCCCGAAUGGAUCCUGUCUCCCAUGUGUUUUGUCCAUCAUGCACCAGGCAUUUGGAACACACUAGCUCACAGAGUUACACGGGCCUUCCAGCAGUGACACAUUUAAUCACACAGAUCAUCAAAACAUCCCAUUCACGAACACUGCUGAACUAACCAGAAGUCUUUUUUUUUUU